CAGCCGCGCGGGCUCCAGGGUCCUCUGGUGGAAGGGCAUGGCGGGGGCGGGCCGGCGGCGCGGGAUCCCUCAGUCUGCCUCCCGUCGGCGCGGGGCGCCAGCCUGCAUCCAACACAAAGGAAGUCCCGGGCAGCGGCGGGGCGCCGAGGGAAGCCUGGCGGCCCCUGCCCGCAGGGGAGAGGCCGGGCGGGCAGGAAGGACGGACGGACGGACGGGCGCGCGGGCGAGCGGGCACCCGGGCGGCGCGGGGCAGGAAUGGGGUCCGAGCCGUGGCUGCCUGGCGCCCGGCGGCGUUCCUCCACCCGCAGGGCUUCGCGGGCCGCGCGGCGAGAGGAAGUUCCAGGGGCAGCUCUGGGCGGCGGCGGCCGCGGCGGCGAGGGGAGCCGCGAGUCCCGCUGAAGUUUGCAGGCGGGCAGGAAAGCGCCGGCUGCUCCUUCCCUCCCUCCGGAUUGGAGAGGGAGGAGGAAGCGAGGGAAGUGCCGCCGACACCGGGCGAGAGGGAGGGGAGGCGAAAGAAAGGAAAGGGGGAGGAGAAAAGGGCCGGCCCGGGAACCACCUGCGGCUCCCGCGGCUGCCGCGCCCAGCGCCCGCAGCCAGUGGCGGCCCCGGCGCCUCAGCGCACCCUGUCGGGGCGGGUGCGGGCGCACAGUCCCGGGACGCCCACGUCGCCGCCCCAACUCCCCUUGGCAGCCCCCGGGCGGUGGGGCAGAGCCCUCGCCCGCCCCCCGGGCCGGGGUGCAGCGCAGUGCGGGCGCCGGGAGGGCGGAGGCGCCAGGACGGCCGCGGCCAGCUCCGCUCGCUCUGCUCACCUGCGCCCCUGCCCACGGCGCUCCGCAGUCAGGAGCGCCCCGCCCCGCGGGGAACGCCCCGGGCCCCUCGGGGUCCCCCUGCUCUCUCCUACUUCCCUUCUGGAAGGUGGCCAACACUUCUGGGCCGCCCGGGUGGACCUCAAAUAGAACGUCUUUAAAUGUCCGGUGGCCAAGGGUUCUGUAGCCGACUAGGAGUCAGCGUCCGACUCGGAACAACUCAAGACCUCUUUUCAGGGGGCGUCCAGUGAGUUUUUUUCAGCAAGGUGACUCCCCCUGUGGCUGCCUGCUACUACAGCUGGAAAGGUCCAAGCUGAAAUGUGACUAAUCUGAGUUUCUUCCACCAAGCAUGUUAGUUAGGGGUGGAGGACUAGAACCUAGAACCCUGAAUUCGAGCCUGGAAGAUAUGUAAGCCACAUGCUAUUGAGAUCGUGGUCAUGGGACACCCGCUAACACAAACCUUCUGGUAGGAAGUUUUUGAGAAGACUGGGUCCAAUAUCCCCAAGCUAAAAUCCCACUGGCCCAUCGCUGUGUUUGCUCAGAAAAGGAAUCUGGGUUCUUUGGUUUCUGCUUUCCAGUUGACCCUGGUUGCUCCUCUGUUUUACGGCAUUUUGGGAGUCGGUCUCCCAGAGCAGCGCUGAUUGUAAUGAGAAGCGCGUUCCCUCUCUGGGGGACAGGAGCAGUGGGAGAAAAAUGGGCCUGGGAAAGAGCUCCUCCAAAUAAAACUUAUUAGACAGAUACGGGUUAUGGUGUUGGUGGUGGUGGUGGUGGUGUUUUGGUCUUUAUCCUGUUGUACAGCGCCUCAUUUUUUACAAUGUGGGCCAGUAACUAUUUCGUAUCACCUACUCUGACCACCUUCAGGGUUGUUAUGAGGCUCAAAGGAACGGCUGCUGUGAAAAAACAUGCUUUGCAAUUUAUGAAGCACUGGAUAAACAUCAGGAACGGUAUAAAAGCAUGCUGCUUACUCAAGAAAUACUAGUUGAGUGCCUGUGUGUUGGGCACUGGCUAGAGAUAAGGUAAUGUGCAAAGCUGGCUCUGUCCCUGCCAUCAUGAGACUCUCGUGUAGUGGACCAUGCAUAACAUUUUUAAAUUAUAUACAAUAUGGCCGGGCGCCGUGGCUCACGCCUGUAAUCCCAGCACUUUGGGAGGCCGAGGAGGGCGGAUCGCCUGAGGUCAGGAGCUUGAGACCAGCCUGGCCAACAUGGUGAAACCCCGUCUCUACUAAAAAUACAACAAUUGGCCGGGCGUGGUGGUGGGGGCCUGUAAUCCCAGCUACUCUGGAGGCUGAGGCAGGAGAAUCGCUUGAACCCGGGAGGCAGAGGUUGCAGUGAGCCGAGAUCAUGCCGUUGCACUCCAGCCUGGGCAACAGAGCCAGACUCUGUCUCAAAAAAAAAAAAAAAUUACAUACAAUAUAAUUUGCCUAUUUAAAGUGUAUAACUCAAUGCUUUUUAGUAUAUUUACAAUGUUGUGCAAACAUCACCAUAAUCACUUUUAGAACAUUUUAAUCACACCAGUCUCAAAAAAACAAUUCUCUUUAGUACUCAGUUCCCUCCCUCCUAAACCAUCACUAGCCAAUUGCAACCACUCAUGUGUCUAUGGAUUUGCCCAUUGUAGAGGUUUCAUAUCAAUGAAAUCAUACAUGUGUGAUUGUUUGUGACUGGCUUCUUUCACUUAGUGUGAUGUUUUCAAAGUUUAUCCAUGGAGUAGCAUGGAUCAGUUUUGAUUCUUUUUUUAAGGCUGCAUAAUAUCCCAUUGUUUGGAUAUGCCACAUUUUGUUUAUCCAUUCAUCAGUUAAUGGACAUUUGGGUGUCCACUUUUUGGCUAUUAUGAUUAAUGCUGCUGUGAACAUGUGUGUACAAGUUUUUGUGUUAACGUGUGUUUUCAUUUCUCUUGGGUACAUACCGAGGAGUGGAAUUGAUGAGUCAUGGUGCCAAUCUGUUUUCCGAAGUGACUGCACCAUUUUACCUCCCAGCCAGCAAUGUAUGAGGGUUCCAGUUUCUUCACAUCCUCGGCAACACUAAUUUUUAUGUCUUUUUUAUUACAGCCAUUCUAGUGGGUAUAAUACCUCAUUGUGGAUUCGAUUUGCAUUUUCCUGAUAGCUAGUGAUAAUGAGCAUCUUUUCAUGAUUUUAUCAGCUACCUGUUUAUCUUCUUUGGAAAAAGAUAACAUUGUAGAAAUGUCUGUUCAGAUUCUUGGCCAUUAUUAAAUCAAAUUUUUGUCCAUUUCUUAUCAAGAUGUAAUAGAUCCUUGAAUAUUCUAGAUACAAGUCCCUUAGGUGUAACAUUUACUUCCUGAUUGCUUUAACAGUCUAUUGUGGGUUUUUUGUUUUUUGUUUUUUGUUUUGAGAUGGAGUCUCGCUCUGUCACCCAGGCUGGAGUGCAAUGGCAGGAUCUUGGCUCACUGCAACCUCCGCCUCCUGGGUUCAAGCGAUUCUCCUGCCUCAGCCUCCCGUGUAGCUGGGAUUACAGGUGCCUGCCACCACGCCCAGCUAAUUUUGUAUUUUUAGUAGAGAUGGAUUUCACCAUGUUGGCCCGGCUGGUGUUGAACUCCUGACCUCAGGUGAUCCACCCACCUCAGCUUCUCAAAGUGCUGGGAUUACAAGCGUGAGCCACAGCACCCGGCCCAGCAUUGUUCUUUAGUUUAUUCCCUCUUCUAUUCCCUUGAGACUUUCCCAUUGGUUUGAAAAGAAUUAUGAUUUAGCCACAUAAACUAAUAAAAAGAGAGCAAGAAUAUUUUUGUAAAUUUGUAAUCCUGGGGCAAUAUCAAUAGAAUUUUUUUUAUAAAAUGAAUGAUUUCACUACUCCAGAAGUGGAAUGUAAACUCUAUACAUAACCAGAACAUGGAAUUAACAGGACUCAUGGGUGUAUCCAUAAAAGCAACUGAAUUUUUAGUCUUCUGCUGUUAAUAAUCUGUUCCAUGAGGAUAGUUCUUCCUCUUCCACAGAAUGAAACUCAGGCAGUCCUAUAACUUUUUUAUUCUCUCAGGUAAUAGAAAAUCCUGUUACUUUAAGAGGAAAAACCCUGCUCUUAAUUCAGUAAUUCAAAUCUUGUCCCCUUCCCCAACAGGGUCUCCUAUGGACAGAAGUGCGGGCAAGGAGCUUUGUUCCUCCCCGAUGUCACCCUCCCACAGCCCACUUGCUAGCAGGCAAGAGAGGGGUGGAGGCCGGCAGUAAGGCAUGUACUGAACUGGACCUCUGGUGGAAUGGGUCACCCACGCUGGGCUUGACUCUUACCAUCAGGGUCCUGCCAACCCUUCAGUGAGACUUUUUCCGAAGAAUCCCUUUUAAAAUGACCUCAAGCUGACCUUCCUGAUGCAGAUUCCACAUAUGGUAUCUGAGACUCACACAGUGUGGUUGGAAGAUAGCACAGUGACCUCCCAGGCACAGCCCUCUGCCAGCCCUCCACUGGCUGCCCUAGGAUGCUGGCCUUCCUCCGAUGGGAGUCGGGCCCAGUCUGCUGUGAGCCAGGAGAAGCCAGCAAGCUCCCUGCGAGGCCUGGAGGAGCCCUUCUCACUCAGCUUGGUGUUCGAUGCCAGUGCCCCCGCCCAUUGUGGGGUGAGGGUGGGACUCUCAGCACAGCCCUGUCCAAAUAAAUCCUCUAAAGCCCUCUUC